GCGGGCACAGCAGCCAGGCUGCCGGAGAGCUGAUCUCGGGGAUUCGGGUGCGGAGCCCUUGGCCUGGAGGCGAUAUGGGUGGUCCGUGGCCCGGUUCAGUCGCUUGCAGCAGCCCGGGGAACAGGCCUGUCUGGCCCUGAGGGAGUCCCCUUUCUGAAGCUGUGGUGCUUGGACGACCUGCUCUCUACAUUGCUGGGCACCUGUAGGUGUCCCUCGAGAGCUCAGUUUUGAGGUUCAAGUCAGUGUGGCCAUGAAGGGGCUGCCUAUUGGGCUGAUGCUGUGACCCUGGAGUCUGCCUCUCCUGCCAGUCCCCCUGCCCGGAACAUGUGGCUGCGGCUUGGCCCGCCCUCGCUGUCCCUGAGCCCCAAGCCCACGGUUGGCAGGAGCCUGUGCCUCACCCUGUGGUUCCUCAGUUUGGCGCUGAGGGCCAGUACCCAGGCCCCAGCACCCACAGUCAACACUCACUUUGGGAAGCUAAGGGGUGCCCGAGUACCACUGCCCAGUGAGAUCCUGGGGCCUGUGGACCAAUACCUGGGGGUGCCCUACGCAGCUCCCCCGAUCGGCGAGAAACGUUUCCUGCCCCCUGAACCACCCCCAUCCUGGUCGGGCAUCCGGAACGCCACACACUUUCCCCCAGUGUGCCCCCAGAACAUCCACACAGCUGUGCCCGAAGUCAUGCUGCCGGUCUGGUUCACUGCCAACUUGGAUAUCGUCGCUACUUACAUCCAGGAGCCCAACGAAGACUGUCUCUACCUGAACGUCUAUGUGCCGACGGAGGAUGUAAAGCGGAUUUCCAAGGAAUGCGCCCGAAAGCCCAACAAGAAAAUUUGUAGGAAAGGAGGAUCCGGCGCUAAGAAACAGGGCGAGGACUUAGCGGAUAAUGACGGGGAUGAAGAUGAAGACAUCCGGGACAGUGGUGCUAAACCCGUCAUGGUCUACAUCCACGGAGGCUCUUACAUGGAAGGGACAGGCAACAUGAUUGAUGGCAGCAUCCUCGCCAGUUAUGGCAAUGUCAUCGUCAUCACCCUCAACUAUCGGGUUGGAGUGCUAGGUUUCCUGAGUACUGGAGAUCAGGCUGCCAAGGGCAACUAUGGGCUCCUUGACCAGAUCCAGGCCCUCCGCUGGGUGAGCGAGAAUAUUGCCUUCUUCGGGGGAGACCCCCGCCGGAUCACUGUCUUUGGCUCGGGCAUUGGUGCAUCCUGCGUCAGCCUCCUCACGUUGUCACAUCACUCAGAGGGACUUUUCCAGAGAGCCAUCAUCCAAAGUGGCUCUGCUCUGUCCAGCUGGGCUGUGAACUACCAACCAGUGAAGUACACCAGCCUGCUGGCAGACAAAGUGGGCUGUAAUGUGCUGGACACCGUGGAUAUGGUGGACUGUCUUCGGCAAAAGAGUGCCAAGGAGCUGGUAGAGCAGGACAUCCAGCCAGCCCGCUACCACGUGGCCUUUGGCCCUGUGAUUGAUGGUGAUGUCAUUCCUGAUGACCCUGAGAUCCUCAUGGAGCAGGGCGAGUUCCUCAACUAUGACAUCAUGCUAGGUGUCAACCAGGGCGAGGGUCUCAAGUUUGUGGAAGGGGUGGUGGACCCUGAGGAUGGUGUCUCUGGCACUGACUUUGACUAUUCCGUCUCCAAUUUUGUGGACAAUCUGUAUGGCUAUCCUGAGGGUAAGGACACCCUGCGAGAGACCAUCAAGUUCAUGUAUACAGACUGGGCAGACCGUGACAACCCUGAGACCCGCCGUAAAACACUGGUGGCACUCUUCACUGACCACCAGUGGGUGGAGCCCUCAGUGGUGACAGCCGAUCUGCAUGCCCGCUACGGCUCGCCUACCUACUUCUACGCCUUCUAUCAUCACUGCCAGAGCCUCAUGAAGCCUGCUUGGUCAGAUGCAGCUCAUGGGGAUGAAGUACCCUAUGUUUUUGGGGUUCCUAUGGUAGGCCCCACUGACCUUUUCCCCUGCAACUUCUCCAAGAAUGAUGUUAUGCUCAGUGCUGUCGUCAUGACCUAUUGGACCAACUUUGCCAAGACUGGUGCAGCGUCAGACGUGGACUCCCUGGCCUUGAGUGACUGACAGAGCAGAGGCCCUCUCCUUCCCCAGGGAUACUUGUUUGCUGCUCUGUGAAUUAGAACUGGAGAAGUCCUUGGGGCCCUGGGAGCGAUUUUUCUACAGGAUUGUGAUCAGUGACUCCCUAUCAACCCUGGGGCAUGGAUUCAGUGGGGCCUCACAGGGUUAGCAUUAUGGGAUUUCAUAUUAUUCUCAGUGACUUGAAAGACUGAACUGGGAGUGUGCUCGGCAAGUAUGAUAGUUGGGUGGGGUUGCUGAUACCUCAGAAAGCAGGAAUAGAAUUCUUCAAAUGACCCUGAUAAAAUGAGGGAGAUGAACCAUCACAAGGAGGACCAUGUUCAGAGAGGACGAACACAGGUAGUGUGUACAAAGACCAAAACCUAGAACUAAUACACUAAUAUGGUACACUGGAGAUGGGCAGUGAUUGACUUGACACAAGUAUAGUUAAAAAGAAGAAGAACUGGGGAGAUGGUGUAAGGGUACAUCACAAGUGAGUCCAUGGUGUAAAACUGGUUUUUCCCCCUCCUUUCCUCACACCCUUCUUUCCUUUCUUUUUUCCAAAACUAAUGUGGAUCCUGCAUAUAGUAACAAAAACACAGCAUGGAGGAUCUGAGAAGUCAUCCAAGUGUGAGUUUUAGAACCAGAAGUCACCCGAGAGUCAUCUAGUCCAACCCAUUUAUUUUAUAGUUGAGGAAAUGGGCCCAGAAAAGCCCGUCACAGUUAGUAUUAGAAACAGACCUAGAAUGCCACCCAGCACUACACGACCCUUGCCAUAGUCCCACUCAACUCGUUCCACUCUACCUGCCAUUGGUCAUACCUUUCAAAGCAUGAUGGGUCUACCCUUGGCCAACACAUUUUUAGCAAAAGUGGAAAGCUAGAGAGGGUCUGGAGAAGAGCAUAAAUAAUGCCACGGGACUAGGUGCUGUGUGUGUGUGCAUGCGUGUGUGUGUGUGUGUGUGUGUGUGUGUGAGAUCUAGAAAGGAAAAAGCUGAUGAGGUAACAUUCAAUGGUUGUAGGGCACCUACCAUGUGAAAAGUGUGCUAUACCCAUCUUCAAAAUUUAACUCCUAAAUAAGGACAGAGCUGAUGACCUGUUCUCCGUUUCUUUUGAGAAUGAUAGAGGGGAAAAUGAGAUCAAGUGAAAUACAAGGAAUAACUUUGCUAUGAAUAGGAAAUGAUCACAAGCACCUAGUGAGUUCUCAAUCGCAGUUGCCAAAUUGAGUGAAUGGCUACUAAGGGAAGCACUGGUAUUUCUCAUCUUCCUGAAAGCAGAGAGCUAGAUUAUAUGACUUUUUUUUUUUUUUUAACAGAGAUGGGGUUUCACCAUGUUGCCCAGGCUGGUCUCAAACUCCUGGGCUCAAGCAAUCCUCCCACCUCGGCCUCCCAAUUGACCUUUUGAGGUCAAUUCAGAGUCUUUGUUCUUAUGUUCCAUCCUUUGAUUGCUCCAUUUGAGAUAUUACGUGGCCUCCUAUUUGAGACCAUACCUGGCCUCCUGUUCUUUAGUGGGGAGUGUACCUCCAAGUUAGGAGUGCUCUCUAUUUUGGGAAGAUUUAGACACUGCCUCUCCUCUAAGAACUCAAGGCGCCAUAGCAAAACCAGCUCCAAUCCUAUUAGGGACCCAUCAGUGAGAGAUUACAAUUGGUCUUCACACCUUUGAAAGGUCUAGGUGGAAGAGGUGACCUCCAAGACAGGCAUGAUUUCAAUCUAAUUGACAGUCAAUUCUGUGCCCCUGUAGCCUCAGGUUCUCAGCCCUGUUGCUGAUGGCCAGCCCUGGGUCCAGCUAAAAUGCCCAGCUCCUUGUUUGAAGUGAAGCUGAGGAUAUACUUGGAUUUAUUUAACAUUGCAAAAAGCAUUAGUGCCUAGAUUCGGUCAGUCCACAUCCCUAGAUUUAUCUGGUUUCUAUUUUAGUCCUUUAAGGAGUUGGACACAGCUAUCAUAUGAUCUGAAUUUGUAGUGUGUGUGAAGGGUCAGAGGUUGGUCACUGUGGAAAUCUCCAUAGCUUGAAGUAUGGUUAUCAGGACUGUAGGCUUGGCCUUGUGCUAGUUUACAUACUGUGGGGGAUAGAAGACACCUAUUUUGGGUUGUGUACUGUCAGGAAGACAAAACGGAACCACAAUCCAAUGAAUGAAAUGCAUGUGCUUCAAUUGUAUGGUAAAGGUUAAAUGGAUUGGAGAAACUGUAAGAAAGGCUAUGAUGGGAUUGGGGUGGGUGGGUAGAGUAGUGGGCAUUCCAAAUUGGAGGGAAACCUCAGCCAAAUCAUGGAGAUGAGAAGGUCUAGGUGUGCUUGAGGGGAUGGGCCAAAAUGGUGGGAAAUUAGCUUGGUAAGGCAGCUCAUGAAGAUCUUCACAACAGAAGAGUUUGGCAAUUAUUGAUUGAGCAACUGGACACCCUGACUGAACUCUUUUGCCAAUAGUUUUAUGGUGGAAAAACAAAACCUCCUCAGCUCCUCUUUCACUCCUUCUCUUCUGCAAGGAAAACGAUUUUCAGACUAGAAAGGACAAGGUGAACACCAGAGAGAAACUCCUGAAGGCAGUCUAGUUCAAGAGAGCCGUAAGCUGCCUUGAGUAACUGCAUCUCAUUGUCUGAGUCAGUAGCAUCCCAGGGCACUUAAGGACUUGCAGCUCAAAUUGCAGGACAACUGGUGGUGGCCCUGAAAACCCCAUGAAGAAGGGAAGAGAUACGUGCUGCAGCCUAGAGAUGGGUAAACAUGGCCCCACUUUGACAGAUGGGAAAAGGUAAACUCCACAAAUUAUAGAUCAAUACAUUUGAUAUUGAUUGAGGGCAAGAUUCUAGGACAAAUGAUUAAAAGGAUGGUUGGUGAGCACUUACAAAAGGAAGCGACGAUCACUCAGUCCCCACAUGGAUUCAGGAAAAACAAAUCAUGCCCCACUGGGUUCAUUUCCCUUGACAGAGUGACUGGACAGGUAGAGGAGGGAAAAGUUAUCACCCACAGCGUAUCUAGAGUUCAACCAAACAUUCUCUCAAUGCUUUUGGGAAAACAUGUAUACAUGUGGGGUGGGUAAAGGUAAACCUAGGCGAAUUCUUAACUGGUUGAAUGACUACAUACAAAAUAGUUCUGUUUUAAUGUCACUAGAUCAAAUUUGCGAAUUACACAAAGUUGGUAAAGUCCCUUAUUUGAACUUCAAAAUGUGGCAGUACAAAUGUAAGAUGUGAGAGAUGUGGCUUAGAGGCAUUUUAGAGUGAAUGAAAGCUCAUGAGUUGAAAGUGUGGUUUGGUUGCUGUAAAAAGUAUUGUGACCUUGGGCCAUAUUACUAAGAGUACAACUUUCAGAACAAAGGAGGUGAUCAUCUUGUGCUACUUUGCACUGAUCAGACCACAUCUGAUGCCCAGUGUUCAGUUAUGAGCACCAGACUUCAAGGGAGAUGUUAACAAAAGUAUAUCCAGAGAAGAGUGAGAAGACUGAAGAAUCCCAGGAGAAAUUUGUCUACUGUCAGUGAGUAAUUACUGGGCUCACAGUAGAUUUGUUCUGCGUGACUUCAGGGCUCCAAGAUCUAAUGGAUGGAAAUUAUAGGAAAGCAGAUUUGGGUUCAACAUGAGGAAGAUGCUCCUUUUCCUUCCUUUUUUAUGAUGAAAAAUUAUAAUAAAAGUUUCAGCUCCUGA